GCAGAGGGUGCGAGCUUGAAGGCGGGAAAAUACGGAAUGGAGCGACAGGGAGUGGACGUGCCCCAUGUGAAAUGCAAAGACCAGGAACCGCAGCCCUUGGGGGAGAGCAAGGAGCAUCCGCGGUGGGAAGAGAACUGCGAGGAGGAAGCUGGUGGAGGGCCAGCUAGUGCCAGUUGCCAGCUGACGGUCCUGGAAGGGAAGUCGGGACUCUACUUCUCCUCUCUGGACUCAAGCAUUGACAUCCUGCAGAAGAGAGCCCAGGAGCUGAUCGAAAACAUCAACAAGAGCCGGCAAAAGGACCAUGCACUCAUGACCAACUUCAGGAACAGCCUGAAGACCAAGGUUUCGGAUCUGACAGAGAAAUUAGAGGAGAGGAUCUAUCAGAUUUAUAAUGACCACAACAAGAUCAUCCAGGAAAAGCUCCAAGAGUUCACCCAGAAAAUGGCAAAGAUCAGCCAUUUGGAGACAGAGCUCAAACAAGUCUGCCACAGCGUGGAGACUGUGUACAAAGACCUGUGUCUCCAGCCUGAGCAGAGCCUAAGACUCAGAUGGGGGCCAGACCACUCUAGGGGAAAGUCCCCACCACGUCCCGGCAACUCACAGCCCCCAGACGUGUUCGUUUCUUCUGUGGCUGAAACUACUUCUCAGGCCACUGCUUCAGAAGUACAGACCAACAGAGAUGGUGAAUGCUGACAGCUGCCGGGAGACUCACGCCUUAGUGACAGUCUCCAGGAGAAGACUGUGAGGCCACCAUUUGGGCCACACUGAGAAAUUGUUUUUCAUGGUUCUAUAAUGCAUCUUGGCAGAAAAAAACAAAAACCCAAAGCUCCUUGUGCUGAACUCCCAAAAUGUAGCAAGUCCAGCCCCUGCCAUAGGCCCAGGCUUCGUGCUCCCCACCCUUGGCAAGUUCUCCCCACCCCCAGCCCCACAGUUUAUUAAAUGUUUGAUUUUCAACCUGGCCACGCUUCCUUGCCACAGAGGCUGAAAGCACCCCUGAGCUCCAAGGAAACACAGCAAGCCCUUUCUUACCCUCGGGAGGGAUAGGAGGGACAGCACAUCGGAAGAGCAGUCACUUGCCUCAGCUGACCUCUGCCCAUCUGAAGCCGCCUCUCCCAGAGAAUCCCACACCCCAUGCCCUGGUGUCUCAUCCUUUGCUCCUCCCCAGCUCCUUGAAGCAGAAGGCAGAUUGUAGCCUCCUUUUUAGAGCCAAUUCUGUUUACUUCCUAAAGUACAAACCUAUUUUUUUUA